GCGAGCCGCGCGGCGCACGGAGCACGGCGGCCGCCUGAGCUCGGCGCGGAGCCCGGAGCCCGCAGCCGACAGUCUCCUGCUCCCGUACGCUGGGCGCCAGCUCCGGCCGUGCUGCCCGGCUGCCUGAGAGCGCGCCCGGCCAUGGAGCCCUCGCACAAAGACGCCGAGACGGCGGCGGCGGCGGCGGCGGUGGCGGCGGCGGACCCCCGGGGGGCGUCCUCGUCCAGCGGGGUGGUGGUGCAGGUCCGCGAGAAGAAGGGCCCCCUGCGCGCCGCCAUCCCCUACAUGCCCUUCCCCGUGGCCGUCAUCUGCCUCUUCCUCAACACUUUCGUGCCGGGACUGGGGACAUUCGUCUCGGCCUUCACUGUGCUGUGCGGGGCCCGCACCGACCUCCCGGACAGGCAUGUGUGCUGCGUCUUCUGGCUGAACAUUGCAGCAGCCCUCAUCCAAAUCCUCACUGCCAUCGUCAUGGUGGGCUGGAUCAUGAGCAUCUUCUGGGGCAUGGACAUGGUCAUCCUUGCCAUUUCCCAAGGCUACAAGGAGCAGGGCAUCCCACAGCAGCUGUGAGCCCACGGGAGCCGCUGGGGAGAUCCAGGGGGGCCCUGUGAGGGCUGCACCAGGCAGCUUUGGGCACAAGGACCUUUACAUGUUCUUUUCUGCCAUUUUCUGGACUGGGGGUGGAAAGGGGGUAUUUUUAAAAAUAUUAUUUAUUUUGAAAACGCAUCUGCUUUUCUCAGCAGGUUGUGAGGGCUGCCAGCCCCUCCUGCUCUGGAAAGCACUGUGGGCGCAGGCACCAGAGCAUCAGAGAGUGGGGUGGAGAUGAGAACGCCCACAGAGAGGCUGGGAUGCUCCGGCAGGCUCCAACUGGCCUUGCUGUACCCACUGCCCACCGCAAAGGCACGCCACGUCUGCUGGGCCGGGCCACACCGGGCCCUGUCUGGGUGAGCAGGGGCUCACCAAGGGGACAGGACUGUGGUAGACCCGUCCUGUGGGACCCCACCUGCCUCAAAAUCUGGUGCCCCGAGUGUUUACUGUGUGGUCUCCUGGGGGCAGCACCAGGGUGUGGGUGAGGAUGGCCAGGCUCCACCCUAGCGUGGAAAGGCCCACUGUGCCCACAGCUGGCCUGAGGCCUCGGGGAGAAGACCAGUCCCACAGGCGUCUCCUGGGCCUGCCUCCCUGACCGCACCCCCCGCCUCCUCGCAGCUGAAAUCUGAGGGCUGGGUGUGUCGUGACCUGUGUUUUCCUGGGAAGGAGAGGAGUAGCUCCUUCCCUGGGGUGAAACUGCCAGAUGUUUAUACACAAAGUUAUUAGACUGAAGCAGGAGUGGGCAGACUAGCAGGCUUUCACCCAAUACUUAACAGCAUUUCUGGCCCACAUUCCUUUUUCUGAAGUCAUUGGGGCCAGAUGUGUCUCCGAAUUGAGAAAUUUUAGAUUUGAGAAAGACAAUGCGAUCCAUUUAUCGUACACUUUCUAACUUCCCGGCAGAGUGUGGAACAUCUCGCCUACCAUCAGGCACGUGAAUAUUUCUGCAGAGAAACAUGUGACUAGUCCCAUUAACUGGGAGCUAUACAAACUGUAAAUAGCCUCACCUCAGUUCAGUCUAAUUUUGCCACUAAGUAACUUAGGGAAAAACUUACCAUUUGAGAGCUUUUAGGGUUUCAGAAUUGCAAGAACAAUUGUAUGGGGUUGUGGACCUUGAUCUGAAAAUCCUGCUUGCAAACAGAUGUGUUAGAGGGUGAAAUUGUCGGCAUUACACAAGGACUCCUUCAGUUGCCAAAAGACCAUGGGCCUCUUUAAGGAGCCCCUCUGUAAGUGAUUGGGACAGGGCUAGAUCCCUAAUGGGGGCUAGGGGUGGGGAGAAUCUAGCAGAAGUUGUCCAGGAUACUGUGGAUCAAGUAUCAAUCUGAAAUUAAGAGAAAUUAGAUACUAAGAGGAUGGACAUUUACAUGUCUGUUUCCUUUCCUUUCAUUUUCAUUCUAACAUAGGAAAUGCUAACAGAUGGGGCUGGCCCAAAGUCAAGCUUCUGACUCCACUUGACACAGUGCCAUUGGGCAUGUCCCUCUCUGAAGGGCUUGUUUGUCUAUCAGAGACUGUCAGAACUCCAUGAGGGCAGGAGAAGGGAUUUUGCAGGAUGAAAGUGCUUGGGAAGUAGUGGCCACCGUUCUGGGGGUUUCAGCCCACCUACCCCAUCCACCGGGCUUUCUAAUCACAGUCCUGCCUGAGAAGCGGGCCCUGCUGCCCACCCCUUAUCAUGGAUCCCUUAGCUACUGUCCGUCUUCCAUUGCUGCCUGGGGCUGGGCUGCCGUUUUUGAACACCUGGCAGUGUCUUUGUCGCGUCCUGUCCUCUCUUCUUACAGACCCCAACCCAGGCCUUUGCCUUCUUCUCUCCUGUUUGGAAGCCUCUGUAUCUUCAAGGUGUGGGAACAGAUUUGGUUUUCUCUAAAAAGCUAGAACCUUCUGCUGUGUGCAGCAGGCAUCCUCCAGGCUGGUGCUGGCUGCUCUCGAGGAAGCUGCGUCAGAGUGGAGCUGCCCCUCUACUCAGAUAAAAUAGCUUCAGCUGCAGGAAGCCGCCCCCUCCCAUGCCCACCAGCCCACAGCCCUUCACCCCACACAGCCCCCAGAGUUUGCCCGACACCCCCUGAGUGAUGACAGGUCUCAGGAGGGGGCCGCCCCCACAAAUGGGAGGCGGAAGCUUAUUUUCCCCGCUUGGGCUGGGGGCGGCUGCUGAGGGGGUGAAGAAGAGAUAGCAAUUUAUGUCGCAUGUUUAGUGACACAAUCCAGAUGCAGGUGGGACUUUCUUGAGUGGCAGGUGUCACCCUGGGUCCCGUGUGGGAUGGUUUAAUACAGGGGUUUGUGUGUUUGUGUGUGUGGAGGGCCACUGCGCCCCCAGAUCCUCCUCUCCCCCGAGGGCUGCGUCUCUAAACCUGGGAAAACAUCAGCCUCAGGAGGAGGCCCCUUUCCGGGUAACUGAUGUGUGGGAGAAGCCAAGAGGCCCCUGCCUGUCUCCUGAAUGAGGCUGUGAGGGUUGCCAUGUGGGCGGGACCGGUUCAAAAUAGCGCCCCCGCCCCUCUAAAUUAGACCGUGGUCUCAGCAUGAUCAUCUUCAGUAGAUAAGGGACAGUGGCUGAUUUACUCCAAAUAGUUCCAGCUGGCCACUCAGACCAGGGCCAGAGUUAACUUCUCAAACACCAGCCAGCUGAAAAUUAGGGUUCUCGUGCAGGCAAGUGCAUGGUUGACACACAGCCCUUUGGUGACAAAGCUGGGCUUUGCCUGCAUAGUGCAGACAAGGCUGUUGGUUCAGAGGCUGCAGGGCACAUUCCAGGUUGGGGCCUUUUGUCGGUCGGAAUUCAAUAGGACAUUCCCUGGCUGUGGGUGUUUAGGGCAGGAAUUACAGGCUUGCAGAGAAAGUCAGAGGCAAUGAGAUGCUCCCAGUACCAAACUGUGACACUGGGAUCAGGGUGGUCAUUCCCUUGGGUCAGAGUGGGACCCUAGAGCCAGAGUGAGCUGUGGGUGGCCUGGGUGUGUCCUGUGGACGGCGGAGACUGUUGAUUUGGAUGUUGAGCUCUGAGUCAGUUUCAGAACCAAGGAUCUCAGGCUGAGAAGGCCAGGUCCCCAUGGGAGCGGCAGGAGUCUGAUGGCUCUGCUGCCAGAGCCUACCCCAGCCUGCCACGCCGCUGACCUUCCCAUGGUAAGGAAGGGGCAGGCAGCAUGGUUCCCACCCUCAGCUGCCCCAGACCCACACAUCCAGCCCCAAGAGCAGCCUCACCCAGGCACAGUGCAGGGCAUUUUAGCUCCUGGGAGGGGAGAUGCCUUUGUGAGUUUCAGAUGUCAGAGGAGAAGCUCCGAGAGAGUAAGUCAUGUGCCCCCAAACACUCAGCUCCUAAGUGGCAGGACAGGCAAGUGGCCAGGUUGGGCCGCCCCCACAGCCUGUGCCGUCCACACACUCACUACAGCACUCCCAGAAGAAGGAGCAGAAUCGCAUGCAGCCCAGAGCAGGUCCUGUGGAGGGGUCCUCACCCCUCAGGAGUAAUAGGGUGAUUAUGUCACAUGUUUAGUGAUACAAUCCCACCUGUGUCUGGAUUGUGUCACUAAACAUGCAACAUAAAUUACCAUCUCUUCUCCAUCCCCUCAGCAGCCGCCCCCACCCCAAGCUGGGAAAAUAAGCUUCUCCCUCCCAUAUGUGGGGGCGGCCCCCUCCUGAGACCUGUCAUCACUUAGGGGGAGUUGGGCAAAACCUCCUAGGAAGGUCCUGGACGCCUCCACCCUGCCCCACAAGGCUCCGUACUCCCACCUGCCUGGGCAGCCCUCACACCCAUGCUCCCUCCUUUAGGCAGGCCCAGAAAGGUGCCCCUUCCUGAGGGUGUUGGGGGAUGGCGGCAGAGAGACAGCUGGUAUUAGGAGCUUCCCCAUCCUAAUGUGCAGGACCAAGUUGCCCGCUCUGCCAGCCAGGGGCUCCAGCCAUGCUGGCACAGGCAUCUCAGAGGUGUGAGAUGAACUCCGCCUCAUGCAGGAUGCCCAGGGCUCGGAAGCAGUAAGGAGGAUGCUACAGAAAGGAACUGCAGAAAGAAAAAAAGCCACAUGGUUAACUUUUCCCCUGGAGGGCAAAGGGGUCCGGCUCUCAAAAAGAAAAGCCAGGCACAGAUCCCAACACCAAGUGUAAGGCAGCACAAAGUGGGUCUGAAACCCCAGGACCGGGUCAAAGGCCUUCCGAAGGCCCGAGGUUCUUGAGGAGGGGAAGCUGAUAGGGCCCUGGUCUUUCUGCACCAGCGUGGCUCUUUAAAAUACAAAACACCCACAAAGCCAAAAACCCUGAAACAUGUUCUUUAGCUAACCCCUUCCCUGCCCAGAUGCCUGCAAUUCUGAGAAUUCACUUCAGUUUUGCCAGAUCCAACCCCUAGGCUUGAGGGUGGAGAGCCAGGCCUCCUCAGGGUCCCUUCUAGGCUCCCAGGCCCACCUUAGGCUUUAAUUGCAUUGGCUGUUUCUUAUGGUGUUAGUGAAUUUUGCAAAGAAAGCCCUGAGCAUUGCAUAAAUGCUUGGGGGCGUGUCAUUUAAAUGGAAGUUCUCCAAUAGUGGCUGAAGGCAGAGUUUACUGUUAUCCCUCCCUCUUGCUGGCUUUGCUGGAGGGCUUUUAUCAGAGAGAUUGGAGGUGGGAGAGCACUUUUAAAGCACACCCCACCCCCUGCACCCGAGCGGCACCUAAGCUUCCCAGAGACCAUGACCUUGUAUGUGGCUGGAGGCCUCAGGCUUAGGGAGCAGCCUGAAGCCUUUGCUGUCAACCCUCCCAGGAAAGAAGCCGGGCCUCAGGCUGAGGAAAAACAGAGUUUCCUCUCCAGAGGGCUCAAUGAGCAGCCAGGUAGUGGCCUCGGGCAGUCCUCACCAGGGGGACACCUCCCUGCUUUGCAUUAACUCAUCAGCAAGCUCAUCGAGAGCUAACGUGGGCCCAGCAGUCCUGUGCUUGGAAAUGAUGCCGUCACCUCCACACUCCUGCUGUUCCAGCCUCUGCAGGUGAAGCUGCAAGGUGAGCAGAGGCAGGCGUGGGGACACACUCUUCAAGGACUGCACUGCCCCUUCUCCCUCCUGAGAGCUCUGUGCACUGGGUUUGGGGAUGAGGCGCCAGCCUGGUCAGGGGAGGUGACUGUGGUCCUUCUGACCAGCUUGGAUCUUUAAAAUAAUCACAAAAAAGCUCAGCCUGAGCAGGUGGGUGCAAGGCUCAGGGGCCUGUGUUUUUCAUCAAUCAGUUUUCUUCCUGCAAGAUUCUUAGAGCUGGAUGUUCACGGGAUCAUGGGGCAUGGAGGUGGUCACGCUCAGACAGUCAUGCACCACCCUCAAUCCCAGGCCCUGCAGAGAUAGGAAGAAUCCCAACCAGAGGGAUUCUUCCCCAAACGUUCCCUUGUGGCCCAAGAGUGAGUUCCGGCCUGAGUGCUGUUAUGACUGCCGGCGUCUCUCCGACUGCCUCUCGCCUCAGUUUAACCAUCUAUAGGUUAGGAACAAAGAAGGGCUUAGGCAGCCAUCGUUUCCCCAUUUCUGUCAGAGCCAAGGGCUUGGAGGCCCAGCCCCAUCCGGGCAAGGGCUGUCCGCUCCUGCCCAGGCCUCACCUCCUCGCUGCAGCUGGCAAGAUUCUUUCUAGCAGAACAGAAACACUGGCCCCCAAUUCCACUCUCCCCUCCUGAUGCUACCGCAGAGGGCAGAAAGGUGCCCUGUAGCGUCCACCAUGUGUGUGUCCUGAGUUUCCAGUGCAAGUCAUCUGGAUUUGCAUUUAGCUAGGGAAACUCGGCCCUCAAACCCUCUCCCUCUCUGCCUGAAUUUGCCAAAAUGCCAACCAUCCGGGCAGGUGUGGAUGCCACAGUCCAUCCCCAUUGCAUUUCACCCCCACAUGGACAGAGGCACACACUCGCACACAUUCCCAGCACCUUUGACUGCUGGGGGAUGCAGGCCAGGGUCUGCCUGGAGCCUCAGGGUUGGGACUUAUCUCCAAAGGAGCCCACACCCCCUCUUCCAGGAUGGGCACUGGCUGGCAGCACUUUUUUCCCUCAUCACAUCCCUGACCCCUGCCCAGCCCACAUGCACAUGCUGUUUCCUGUCUCCAGGGCCCUAGCCUGUGGAUCUCUUCCUCCCAUGCACUCCUAGGGUGAAUGGGCUCAGCACCAAACCUGGCUGUGCCCAUUCCCCACAACCCCAGCUUGGCCUCCUGUGGGAAGGAGAAGGCAGACCUGCCCAGAGGAGAGGGGCAGUGUUCCCACCCACCUGCUCCAGCACAGGAACCAGGGAGGAAAGAAGGGAGAGGGAGGUUCCAUUCACCGUUUUCUGGGUUAGCGCUUGAUUGGAUGUUUCAAGCAAGGGACAAGGUGAUGGUGGCUGUAAUAGGCUCCUCGUGGGCACCGUCACCCCAGAAGGCCUGGGCACCCAUGAGAACCUGUGGCCAGCCCUUUUCAUUGGCUGAGUUCCCUGCUGUUGUGCGUGGUGCCAUUUUUUUUUUAAACAACAUAUAUAAAAACAAAACAACUGGUUCUGUGUGUAUCAACUUAAUUUGCAUAUGAAUGAGUGUUGUGUUGUGAUUUGCAGUGUUUUGACACCGUGAUUGGCUUUGUUUGGGUCUCUCUUCUUUCUGUGAAAUUAACUGCUGUGCGUUUUCACUGUUCUUAGAGAAGACCCUGAGCUCCUGGGGUUUUCUUGUCUCACUUCUACCCUGACCUGCUGGGAGCCCACCCCACCCCAGUCCAGCCAUGAGGGUAUUUCCAGCCUAUUCCAAUGACUGAAACCCUUCUUGGAAGAAAACGUCUAAUGUCGGGGACGUAGGGACGCUUCCAGACUUGCCCUGGCCGGAACCCUGCAGCCUGGGGCCCCAGCCCGCCUGCAGCUCAGCUUUCCCCAACACCCUCAGGACCCAGCCCCAGCCCCGGCAGACCUUCCCUGGGAGCUGCUUAGGUGGUCUCCACAGCGCCCUCUAGGGGCCAAGCAGGGUUCCAGAUUCUCCAGCCUUCUGCCAGCUUUAAAACCCUUCACUCAAGCAGCAUUACUGUACAUGCAAUGAAAAAUACUAUAUAUGACAGUCAAAACCUGUGUACAUAUUUCCAUGUACAUAUUUAUACAUACACACACCUUCCUAUUAUAAAUAUAUAAAGCAUGACAUCUCUUUGGCAUUCCAAGUUUGUGUUUUUUUAAAUCCUUGGAAAUACGGCUUUGGAAACCUUUUUCUUCCUUUCCCUCUUUUCUAUGUUGUAAUAAACAUUCAUGUGACCUUUCUGGUAGUUUCUCAAA